GUAAGUUGAAGCGGGUCAGCGGCACGGAAGGGUUGCUCCAGGUGGGAUAGGAAAUUAAAAAGCGUCAGAUCUGGAAGGGGCCUUAUAUGCUAUUGGCCCCUUUCGCUUUACGGAUCGGUAAAUUGAGGCCUGGAGCGGGAAAAAGAAUGGAAGACCCUGUCGUCCUCGUGCCUUCCCAAGGCUUCCGAAGCGCGCACACACGCACACACCUCGAUUUCGGGGCUGCCUCUAUAGCCUCAGUCCGUAAAAUCGUAUCGCUAGGUAGGAGUGGUGCUCUAACUGUCCAGUCCCCUCGCUCACUUCCUCUUCUAUCCGUGCCGCUUUCAGCCGUUCUUUGCCAAGUUCCCUCCGAAGUCCUCUGAGCUCCUGCAUUGUAGCGGGAAGCGGCAGUGAGCAUCAUGGAUACCGACUUAUAUGAUGAGUUUGGGAAUUAUAUUGGACCAGAGCUUGAUUCUGAUGAAGAUGAUGAUGAAUUGGGUAGAGAGACCAAAGAUCUUGAUGAGAUGGAUGAUGAUGACGACGACGAUGACGUAGGAGAUCAUGACGAUGACCACCCUGGGAUGGAGGUGGUGCUGCAUGAGGACAAGAAGUACUACCCAACAGCCGAGGAGGUGUAUGGUCCUGAGGUGGAGACCAUAGUUCAAGAGGAAGACACUCAGCCUCUCACAGAACCCAUUAUUAAGCCAGUGAAAACCAAGAAAUUCACUCUGAUGGAGCAGACAUUACCUGUUACGGUGUAUGAGAUGGAUUUCUUGGCGGAUCUGAUGGAUAACUCAGAGCUCAUCAGAAAUGUGACCCUUUGUGGACAUCUCCACCAUGGCAAGACAUGUUUUGUGGAUUGUUUAAUUGAACAGACUCACCCGGAAAUCAGAAAGCGCUAUGACCAAGAUCUGUGCUAUACUGACAUCCUCUUCACAGAGCAAGAGAGAGGUGUAGGCAUCAAAAGCACUCCUGUGACAGUGGUCUUGCCAGACACCAAAGGAAAAUCUUAUCUCUUCAAUAUCAUGGACACUCCAGGACAUGUGAAUUUCUCUGAUGAGGUCACAGCUGGCUUGCGCAUCUCAGAUGGAGUGGUCCUUUUCAUUGAUGCUGCUGAGGGGGUGAUGCUGAACACAGAGCGGCUGAUCAAGCAUGCGGUGCAGGAGAGGCUGGCAGUCACUGUGUGCAUCAACAAGAUUGACCGGCUGAUCCUGGAGCUGAAGCUGCCUCCAACUGAUGCUUAUUACAAGCUGCGCCACAUUGUGGAUGAGGUCAAUGGAUUAAUAAGCAUGUAUUCCACUGAUGAGAACCUGAUCCUUUCCCCACUCCUGGGUAACGUCUGCUUCUCCAGCUCCCAGUACAGCAUCUGCUUCACGCUGGGCUCCUUUGCCAAGAUCUAUGCCGACACCUUUGGUGACAUUAAUUACCAAGAAUUUGCUAAAAGACUCUGGGGUGACAUCUACUUCAACCCUAAGACGCGAAAGUUCACCAAAAAGGCCCCAACUAGCAGCUCCCAGAGAAGUUUCGUGGAGUUUAUCUUGGAGCCUCUUUAUAAGAUCCUCGCCCAGGUUGUAGGUGACGUGGACACCAGCCUCCCACGGACCCUAGACGAGCUUGGCAUCCACCUGACGAAGGAGGAGCUGAAGCUGAACAUCCGCCCCUUGCUCAGGCUGGUCUGCAAAAAGUUCUUUGGCGAGUUCACAGGCUUUGUGGACAUGUGUGUGCAGCAUAUCCCUUCUCCAAAGGUGGGCGCCAAGCCCAAGAUUGAGCACACCUACACCGGUGGUGUGGACUCCGACCUCGGCGAGGCUAUGAGUGACUGUGACCCUGAUGGCCCCCUGAUGUGCCACACUACUAAGAUGUACAGCACAGAUGAUGGAGUCCAGUUUCACGCCUUUGGCCGGGUGCUGAGUGGCACCAUUCAUGCUGGGCAGCCUGUGAAGGUACUGGGGGAGAACUACACCCUGGAGGAUGAGGAAGACUCCCAGAUAUGCACCGUGGGCCGCCUUUGGAUCUCUGUGGCCAGGUACCACAUCGAGGUGAACCGUGUUCCUGCUGGCAACUGGGUUCUGAUUGAAGGUGUUGAUCAACCAAUUGUGAAGACAGCAACCAUAACCGAACCCCGAGGCAAUGAGGAGGCUCAGAUUUUCCGACCCUUGAAGUUCAAUACCACAUCUGUUAUCAAGAUUGCUGUGGAGCCAGUCAACCCCUCAGAGCUGCCCAAGAUGCUUGAUGGCCUGCGCAAGGUCAACAAGAGCUAUCCAUCCCUCACCACCAAGGUGGAGGAGUCUGGCGAGCAUGUGAUCCUGGGCACUGGGGAGCUCUACCUGGACUGUGUGAUGCAUGAUUUGCGGAAGAUGUACUCAGAGAUAGACAUCAAGGUGGCUGACCCAGUUGUCACGUUUUGUGAGACGGUGGUGGAAACAUCCUCCCUCAAGUGCUUUGCUGAAACGCCUAAUAAGAAGAACAAGAUCACCAUGAUUGCUGAGCCUCUUGAGAAGGGCCUGGCAGAGGACAUAGAGAAUGAGGUGGUCCAGAUUACGUGGAACAGGAAGAAGCUGGGAGAGUUCUUCCAGACCAAGUACGAUUGGGAUCUGCUGGCUGCCCGUUCCAUCUGGGCUUUUGGCCCUGAUGCGACUGGCCCCAACAUUCUGGUGGAUGAUACUCUGCCCUCUGAGGUGGACAAGGCUCUUCUUGGUUCAGUGAAGGACAGCAUCGUUCAAGGUUUCCAGUGGGGAACCAGGGAGGGCCCCCUCUGUGAUGAAUUGAUUCGGAAUGUCAAGUUUAAGAUCCUGGAUGCGGUGGUUGCCCAGGAGCCCCUGCACCGGGGCGGGGGCCAGAUCAUCCCCACAGCCAGGAGAGUCGUCUACUCUGCCUUCCUCAUGGCUACUCCUCGUCUGAUGGAGCCUUACUACUUUGUAGAGGUCCAGGCCCCUGCAGAUUGCGUCUCUGCAGUUUAUACCGUCCUGGCCAGGCGCAGGGGGCACGUGACUCAGGAUGCACCCAUCCCAGGCUCCCCUCUGUACACCAUCAAAGCUUUUAUCCCGGCCAUCGACUCUUUUGGCUUUGAGACUGAUCUCCGGACUCACACCCAGGGACAAGCCUUUUCUCUGUCUGUCUUCCACCACUGGCAGAUUGUGCCUGGUGAUCCCCUGGACAAGAGCAUUGUCAUCCGCCCCUUGGAGCCACAGCCAGCUCCUCACCUGGCCCGGGAAUUCAUGAUCAAAACCCGCCGUAGGAAGGGCCUCAGUGAAGAUGUGAGCAUCAGCAAAUUCUUCGAUGAUCCUAUGUUGCUGGAACUUGCCAAACAGGAUGUUGUGCUCAAUUACCCCAUGUGAGUGCGUGGACUCCUGGGAGCUCCUGCUCCCUACAGUGGGCUGCAACUCCUGUACUUGAAGCUGAGACCUCAUAUGACGUGGCCUUCGUGUUGUCAGAGAGUGUCUGGAAGCUGCUGUUGCCAUCUUGAACAACUCACCAACCUCCAACCCAGAGCCCCAGUGAGAGAGGAGCAUUUGGCCUCCUGCUUCCUUCUGUGGCCUCUGCCGGGCUCCAUUCCCAAGGAAAAGAGAGGAGCUUGGGCUCACAGAAAGAGAAGGGGAUGAAACCCCAAGGGGCCCUAUCUUUGGGAUUUACAUGGAAUUUUAUUUUCUACAAGUUUGACCUUAGCCAUGGUUUGCAAGUGAACAGAACAUUCUGACCUCUGUCUUGCUCUGCUCCUUUCAUCCUCGUCUCCCCUGCCCCGUCUGGUGCUUACAUUCUGAAUAUAUGUCAUCUCCCAAGAGGCUUCACUGCCUCUGCUUCCAGCUGCAGCCUCCUUCCUGCCUGGGUCCCCAGGGAAGCCGCCUGCCUUUUAAUUCAGUGUUCCCAUGAGCGCCAAGGCCCCAUUAUUGCCCCCUUGCUCCCACUCCAUGCUGCUUCUGGGUGGAACCUAAGAUGGCUUGGGAGUUGUUGGGUUCCUGCGAUCAGAAGUCUACCCCACCACCUCCUCAGGAAACUGCUGCCUCCCCUAAGAAUCUUCCUUGCCCUGGAGUAGGGGGCCAGAGCACUUUGAUUUCCAGCCAUUUACUCCAAGUCCUCUCCCCAGCUACCACCAGUCCCUUACUCUGUUCUCCCCCAGUGAAAAAGAGUCUGUUGAUUUUCCUCAAAACUGCUUUAUUAGGAAUGUACCAGGGAUUGAGUUAGGGGAGUUGGACAGCCCCGGCUCCUAUAGGAGUCCUACUUCUCUCCAGCAUCCUGUGCCAUCCUCUUGACGUAAUCGCUGUACAUUGUGUACACAGCACCUGUGUGAGAGAAAAGAAAUAAUGCCCCUUGGCAUCAAACCCUUCACCCGUCCUCUGGCUCUCAGGCGUCCUAGGGGUUCACCUCUAGCUGCUCCCUUGAGAGUCCAGCUUCCCGCUCAUCUUUCUGCCCCAGGUCCCAACAGCUGCUUCAAGCAUCUGACCACACAACCUGGGGAAACCACUUAUCUGACAGUUCACGAAACACUUUCACAUGUAUUGUGUAUCUGAGAAACCUCACAGCAGCCUGCAAGGUAGGCAGGCCAGGGGUGGUUAUUGUCAUGUUACACAUCAGGAAACUGAGGCUCAGUGAGAAAGAUUUGUCCACUGUCACACAGUUAGCAAGUGGCUGUCUGCUUUUUAAUCUCAAGAGGAAGAGAAAUUCAA